AACAGUUCUGACGUGAGAGGACAAGAAACACAAGCAAAUAUAAAACAUUCAAUUCUAAGAGAAGUUCAUCAGAGACAUCCUUCAGGAUUGUGAGCUGGAUUUUCCUCUACGUGCUUCAGUCUUCUCUACACAAAGAGCUGCAAACCAGGUCUUUGUUUUGCACUCUUAUUUCAAGCAGAAUGAGUGCUCCUAAACUCCUCUCUCUGGGCUGUAUCUUCUUCCCCUUGCUACUUUUUCAGCAGGCCCGGGCUCAAUUCCCAAGACAGUGUGCCACUGUUGAGGCUUUGAGAAGUGGUAUGUGUUGCCCAGACCUGUCCCCUGUGUCUGGGCCUGGGACAGACCGCUGUGGCUCAUCAUCAGGGAGGGGCAGAUGUGAGGCAGUGACUGCAGACUCCCGGCCCCACAGCCCUCAGUAUCCCCAUGAUGGCAGAGAUGAUCGGGAGGUCUGGCCCUUGCGCUUCUUCAAUAGGACAUGUCACUGCAACGGCAAUUUCUCAGGACACAACUGUGGGACGUGCCGUCCUGGCUGGAGAGGAGCUGCCUGUGACCAGAGGGUUCUCAUAGUCAGGAGAAAUCUUCUGGACUUAAGUAAAGAAGAAAAGAACCACUUUGUCCGGGCCCUGGAUAUGGCAAAGCGCACAACUCACCCUUUAUUUGUCAUUGCCACCAGGAGAUCAGAAGAAAUACUGGGGCCAGAUGGCAACACGCCACAAUUUGAGAACAUUUCCAUUUAUAACUACUUUGUUUGGACACACUAUUACUCAGUCAAAAAGACUUUCCUUGGGGUAGGACAGGAAAGCUUUGGUGAAGUGGAUUUCUCUCAUGAGGGACCAGCUUUUCUCACAUGGCACAGGUACCACCUCCUGCGUCUGGAGAAAGACAUGCAGGAAAUGUUGCAAGAGCCUUCUUUCUCCCUUCCUUACUGGAAUUUUGCAACGGGGAAAAAUGUCUGUGAUAUCUGCACGGAUGACUUGAUGGGAUCCAGAAGCAACUUUGAUUCCACUCUAAUAAGCCCAAACUCUGUCUUUUCUCAAUGGCGAGUGGUCUGUGACUCCUUGGAAGAUUAUGAUACCCUGGGAACACUUUGUAACAGCACCGAGGAUGGGCCAAUUAGGAGAAAUCCAGCUGGAAAUGUGGCCAGACCAAUGGUGCAACGUCUUCCUGAACCACAGGAUGUCGCUCAGUGCUUGGAAGUUGGUUUAUUUGACACGCCUCCUUUUUAUUCCAACUCUACAAACAGUUUCCGAAACACAGUGGAAGGUUACAGUGACCCCACGGGAAAGUAUGACCCUGCUGUUCGAAGUCUUCACAAUUUGGCUCAUCUAUUCCUGAAUGGAACAGGGGGACAAACCCAUUUGUCUCCAAAUGAUCCUAUUUUUGUCCUCCUGCACACCUUCACAGAUGCAGUCUUUGAUGAAUGGCUGAGGAGAUACAAUGCUGAUAUAUCCACAUUUCCAUUGGAAAAUGCCCCUAUUGGACAUAAUAGACAAUACAACAUGGUGCCAUUCUGGCCCCCAGUCACCAACACAGAAAUGUUUGUUACUGCUCCAGACAACCUGGGAUACACUUAUGAAAUUCAAUGGCCAAGUCGGGAGUUUAGUGUACCUGAGAUAAUUGCCAUAGCAGUAGUUGGCGCUUUGUUACUGGUUGCACUCAUUUUUGGGACUGCUUCUUAUCUGAUUCGUGCCAGACGCAGUAUGGAUGAAGCUAACCAGCCUCUCCUCACUGAUCAGUAUCAAUGCUAUGCUGAAGAAUAUGAAAAACUCCAGAAUCCUAAUCAGUCUGUGGUCUAACAAAUGCCCUACUCUCUUAUGCAUUAGUAUCACAAAACCACCUGGUUGAAUAUAAUAGAUUGAGUUAUUAACUGUAUUUUCUUUCACUUUAUUACCUUCUUUCUAAUACAAGCAUAUGUUAGCAUUAAAGUUCUAGGCAUACUUUUCAAAGCUGGGAAGACCCUUUCAGAAUCUUUUCAAUGGGUUUUAAUUUUCAGUUCUAUUUAAAAUGGUGAAUGACACUAAACUCCAUGAUAUUUAAGGAUAGUGUGAAGAUCUUUGGCAUGAUUUAAAGGUUGAGUAUGUGAAGAUAUAAGUAAGUGAACUACCAUGCUUUGUUUACGUGUAAAGGAAAAUAAUGUUUGAUAGUAAAUGUCCACUUAAAAUACAUGAAUGGGCAUUUCUAAAAUGUUAAAACAUAAACACAUUUCCAUUCAUGGAUAUUUGUCAACAGAUUUAAAGAAAACCACAGUUAUUAAUUAAAGAAAAUUAAUUAUGUGUAGUUAUAAACCAAUGAAAUUUUGAUUAACCUUUUCAAAUUAAUGUUCCAGUUUGAAGACCAAUCAAAUAUAUUAUUUAGUCAACAUAUACUAUUUAGUCUCAGGUUCAAGGCUACAACAAAAAUCACCAUCUUUGUCAAACUUUGGAGAGGGAAAAUCUUCACUUUCUUAAGCAACAAUGGAUAUUGCCUGUGUUUGCCACUGUGUUUCCCUGCCUCUCAAUUCGCUGAAAAAGGAACUACCUAUCCUUACAUUUCACCUACUAAUGUCUCUUCUAACAUCUUAGAGGUCCAUGGAGAAGGCAUAUGGAGAACAUGUUUUAUACUGCUCUAUAAAUAGUAUUCCAAUCACUGUGCUUAAUUUAAAUAGCAUUAUCUUAUCAUUUAUCAGCCUUUUAUGUAUUUUCCAAGUAAAAUAUUAACAUAUUAUUUCAUUGGUCUUCUUUUUUAUCUGGUUCUAUAUGAAUGCUAUUUUUUCCCUUCUCUUCUAACAUGAAAUAUAUUUUCUCUUUUUGAUCUUGUGCUAUGAAACAAUCUUCCAAAGAACUGUAUAAGGUGGUCAUAAGUGAAUAUUUUAAUUAAAAUUGGUAAAAAUAAAUAAUAACAGUAAUAAUCAUGCACUAUA